GCAGACGGCGCUCGCAGCGCCCCCGGCCCCCAGGCGGCGCGGCUGGUCCCCAGGGGUCUGCGGGCGACUGCGCGGCUGAGGCGCCCGAGUGCGGUACUGGCGGCGGGCGGCGGGCAGCCAUGGCGGAGGCCGCGUCGCCGCACUUGUCGCUGCCCUCGGGGCUGCUGGAGCUCUGCGCGCUGCUGGGCGCCCCCCGGGACAGUCUCCGAAGUCUCGAGCAGGUUGCUUAUAAAAAGGGAGUCAAACAUCUUUCUGCUCUUCUUGAUCCAGAGGUCCUGUCCAUUUUCGUGCCUCCUUUUAUCAGUAAAGAGGACAGUCAAAUGGCCGGUGCCAACUGCGGCACUCUCGGUAAAACCCGGAUGCGCUCCUUGAGAAAGAAGAGAGAGAAGCCCAGACCAGAGCAGUGGAAGGGCCUCCCGGGGCCCCCCAGAGCGCCAGAGCCUGAGGAUGUCGCCGUCCCGGGCGGCGUGGACCUCCUCACCCUGCCGCAGCUGUGCUUCCCAGGGGGUGUGUGCGUGGCCACUGAACCUAAGGAGGAUUGCGUCCACUUCCUGGUGCUGACCGAUGUCUGCGGGAAUAGGACCUAUGGCGUGGUGGCCCAGUACUACCGGCCCCUGCAUGAUGAGUACUGUUUCUACAAUGGCAAAACGCACCGGGAGUGUCCUGGCUGCUUCGUGCCCUUCGCGGUGUGCGUGGUCUCCAGGUUUCCCUAUUACAACUCCCUCAAGGACUGCCUUUCCUGUUUAUUGGCUCUUCUGAAGCCCUGUAAAGAUUUUGAAGUGGACAGUCAUAUAAAAGAUUUCGCUGCGAAGCUGUCUUUAAUACCCAGCCCGCCACCUGGACCGCUCCAUUUGGUAUUUAACAUGAAGUCGCUCCAGAUUGUGUUACCUGCCCGAGCAGACCCCGAAAGCCCCAUCCUGGACCUGGACCUUCACCUGCCCUUGCUGUGCUUCAGGCCUGAGAAGGUGCUACAGAUCCUGACAUGCAUCCUGACGGAACAGCGGAUCGUCUUCUUCUCCUCGGACUGGGCUCUGCUGACGCUGGUCACUGAGUGCUUCAUGGCCUACCUGUAUCCGCUGCAGUGGCAGCACCCCUUCGUGCCCAUCCUGUCGGACCAGAUGCUGGAUUUCGUCAUGGCCCCCACGUCCUUCCUGAUGGGCUGCCAUCUCGACCACUUCGAAGAAGUCAGCAAGGAAGCCGACGGUUUAGUUCUGAUAAAUAUUGAUCAUGGGAGCAUCACCUACUCCAAGUCCACGGACGAUAACGUGGACAUUCCUGAUGUCCCCCUCCUGGCAGCCCAGACGUUUAUUCAGAGGGUGCAGAGCCUCCAGCUCCACCAUGAGCUGCACGCCGCCCACCUCCUCUCCAGCACAGACCUGAAGGAGGGCCGAGCCCACCGGCGGUCCUGGCAGCAGAAACUCAACUGCCAGAUACAGCAGACCACCCUGCAGCUGCUCGUGAGCAUCUUCAGGGAUGUAAAGAAUCAUUUAAACUAUGAACACAGAGUCUUUAAUAGUGAAGAAUUUCUCAAAACCAGGGCUCCAGGGGACCAUCAGUUUUAUAAGCAGGUCUUAGACACCUACAUGUUCCAUUCUUUUCUUAAAGCCCGGCUCAAUAGGAGGAUGGACGCCUUUGCUCAGAUGGACCUCGACACCCAGUCGGAGGAGGACAGAAUAAAUGGAAUGCUUCUAAGUCCAAGGAGACCGACCGUUGAGAAAAGAGCCUCCCGGAAGUCCUCGCACCUGCAUGUCACCCACAGGCGCAUGGUGGUCAGCAUGCCCAACCUGCAGGACAUUGCCAUGCCUGAGCUGGCACCCAGGAACUCCUCGCUCCGGCUGACGGACACCGCAGGCUGUAGGGGCAGCAGCGCAGUUCUGAAUGUCACGCCGAAGUCCCCGUAUACAUUCAAGAUUCCCGAAAUCCACUUUCCGCUGGAGAGCAAGUGCGUGCAGGCAUACCAUGCCCACUUUGUCUCCAUGCUGAGCGAGGCCAUGUGCUUUCUGGCCCCCGAUAACUCUCUGCUCCUGGCCCGCUAUUUGUACCUCCGAGGGCUCGUUUAUCUGAUGCAGGGACAGCUGCUGAACGCCCUCUUGGACUUCCAGAAUCUGUAUAAAACAGACAUACGGAUCUUUCCCACUGAUUUGGUGAAGAGGACGGUGGAAUCCAUGUCUGCCCCUGAGUGGGAGGGGGCUGAGCAGGCGCCGGAGCUGAUGAGGCUCAUCAGCGAGAUCCUGGACAAGCCGCACGAGGCCUCGAAGCUGGACGACCACGUGAAGAAGUUCAAGCUGCCCAAGAAGCACAUGCAGCUGGGCGACUUCAUGAAGCGGGUCCAGGAGUCAGGGAUCGUGAAGGACGCCAGCAUCAUACACCGGCUGUUCGAGGCCUUGACUGUAGGACAGGAGAAACAAAUCGACCCAGAAACAUUCAAAGAUUUCUACAACUGCUGGAAGGAGACGGAAGCAGAAGCCCAGGAGGUCAGUCUGCCGUGGCUGGUGAUGGAACACCUGGAUAAAAACGAGUGUGUGUGUAAGUUGUCCAGCUCCGUCAAGACAAACCUAGGCGUUGGCAAGAUCGCCAUGACCCAGAAGCGCCUGUUCCUCCUAACCGAAGGAAGGCCAGGCUACUUGGAGAUUUCCACCUUCAGAAAUAUAGAGGAGGUCAGGAGAACCACUACUACAUUUCUACUUCGGAGAAUACCCACUUUAAAAAUCAGAGUGGCGUCCAAGAAAGAAGUCUUCGAAGCCAACCUGAAAACCGAGUGUGACCUUUGGCACCUGAUGGUGAAGGAGAUGUGGGCUGGGAAGAAGCUGGCCGAUGACCACAAGGACCCUCACUACGUCCAGCAGGCGCUGACCAACGUCUUGCUGAUGGACGCCGUCGUGGGCACACUGCAGUCACCAGGCGCCAUCUACGCUGCCUCCAAGUUAUCCUACUUUGAUAAGAUGAGUAACGAAAUGCCCAUGACGCUUCCGGAGACAACCCUGGAAACACUGAAGCAUAAAAUCAACCCCUCGGCGGGGGAGGCGUUCCCACAAGCGGUGGACGUGCUGCUCUACACUCCAGGGCAUCUUGACCCAGCCGAAAAAGUUGAAGAUGCUCACCCCAAGUUAUGGUGUGCUCUGAGCGAAGGCAAGGUGACCGUGUUCAAUGCUUCUUCAUGGACCAUCCACCAGCACUCCUUUAAAGUGGGCACUGCAAAAGUGAACUGCAUGGUGAUGGCCGACCAGAACCAGGUGUGGGUUGGCUCGGAAGACUCCGUCAUCUACAUCAUCAACGUCCACAGCAUGUCCUGCAACAAGCAGCUCACAGCCCACUGCUCCAGUGUCACGGAUUUGAUUGUGCAGGACGGACAGGAGGCACCCAGCAACGUGUACUCGUGCAGCAUGGACGGCAUGGUGCUGGUGUGGAAUGUGAGCACACUGCAGGUGACCAGCCGCUUCCAGCUGCCGCGAGGUGGCCUGACGUCCAUCAGACUGCACGGCGGCCGCCUGUGGUGCUGCACAGGUAACAGCAUCAUGGUCAUGAAAAUGAAUGGAUCCCUCCAUCAAGAAUUGAAGAUUGAGGAGAACUUCAAAGACACCAGUACCUCCUUCCUGGCCUUCCAGCUCCUUCCUGAGGAGGAGCAGCUGUGGGCGGCCUGUGCAGGACGCAGCGAGGUUUACAUCUGGAGCCUGAAGGACCUGGCCCAGCCCCCGCAGAGGGUGCCCCUCGAGGACUGCUCUGAGAUCAACUGCAUGAUCCGGGUGAAGAAGCAGGUAGGGUGGAGGGCCCGCCAUCCCCAGCAUCCCCGGCAGGUCUCGCUUGCCCUGGCCGCAUCCCCAUGCUCCCGAGAGCCAGCCGCACGCCCUCGUGCCCUCCUGCCUUCGCCUCUCAGGGUUCCCCUCCUAACAGGCACGUGCAGGGUUGGUGCCAACGGGCCCACAGGUCACCAUGUGCUGGUUUCAUGGUGUGGUCCAAGCACUCCACAGCGCAUUCCCCCAAACUGGAUGGCUUCAAAUGACAGAACUUAAUUUUCUCACAGUUCUCGACGCUGGAGGUCCAAAACCAAGGUGUCGGCAGAGCCGCUUCCCUCGGGGGCUCGGGGGGAGCGUGCACUCCAGGCCCUUCUCUCCCCCACCCGCUCAUGUGGCCGCCGUCCUUGGCGUGCCCUGGCUGUGGACGUGGCACUCUAACCUGUGCCUGCACCACAUGGCACUCUCUCUCCCUGUGUGUGUCUCUUAUGGGGAUGCUGGUCGUACUGGAUUAACCAGUGUGACCACAUCUGAACUAUCUGCAGACUCUACUUCCAAAGAAGCUCACAUUCUGAGGUUCAGAGGAUAUGGAUUUGGGGGGACACUGUUCAACCCAUUACAGUCUGCCCUCUGGCCCCCUAAAUCCACAUCUGUUCCACAUGCAAAAUACACCCCCUCCAUCACUACAUCCCCCGAAGUCCCAGUCCCUCCAGUGUCAGUUCUGAGCCCCAAAUCUCCAAGUGAAGCCAAAGCCCUCCGAUGUGGGUGAGCCGUGGGCGGGUCCCACCUGGGGCAGAACCAACCCCUCUUGCACCGUGAACCUGCGCAGCUAGAACAGGCUGUCUCUUCCCAAAACACAAGGCUGGGCCAGGCAGAGGUUAGACAUUCUCAUCCGAAAAGGGAGAAAUUGGAAGGAAAGCUGGACUUCCAGGCCCCGAGCAAGUCGGAGACACGGCGGGGGUGGGGCGGAAUUCGUUUAGUGUUUUCCCCCAUAACUUAAUUGGGGUAUAAUUGAUGAAUAAAAAUUAUAUAUAUCUAAGGUAUACAAGGUGAUAUUUCAGUAUACAUUGUGAAAUAAUCACAAGCUAAUUACCAUAUCUGUCACCUCACACAGGUGGCUGUUGUUUGGUGAGAACACUUAAGAUGCACCCCAGCACUUUUCCAGCACGCAGUGCAGUCUUCUUCCCCAGAGGCCCCUCGGCCAUUAGGUUCUAAGCCCGAGAAGGGUCCUGUGCACCUGCCAGGCGGCCCUGACCCUCAGGCGGCAGAGGCCCUGUCCAGGAAGGACAUAGAUUUGGAGGCACACGCGUCAAUUCUGGGUAGCCGGGCAAAGCCCUGGUGCUCUUGGGAGGGGCUUCUUUCCCUGCUGACCCCUCCCGUUUCUCCCUGGCAGGUCUGGGUGGGCAGCCGAGGGCUGGGGCAGGGAACACCCAAGGGGAAAAUCUACGUGAUUGACGCCGAGAGGAAGACCGUGGAGAAGGAGCUGGUGGCGCACAUGGACACCGUGAGGACGCUGUGCUCGGCUGAGGACAGAUACGUGCUGAGUGGGUCGGGCAGGGAGGAGGGGAAAGUCGCCAUUUGGAAAGGCGAAUAAACGUGGCUGAGUCUGCCAAGUGGAACUGUGCCCUAUGUGUGGGGACUGGCUGCCCCCUAGAGCCUGCCAGGAGCAGAAGCCUGGAGGGGUGGCAGGGCAGAGCAGCCCAGGCUCAGCAUGGAGCCCACUUACCGUGUGGCCAGCCGCGAGACCCAUGGCCACGCACCUUCUCUCAGGCCUUCGGGCCCCCUGGUUAAACUGCACCAAGGGUGUUUCCUGUUGGGGUGUGUCUCAGGCAGGCAGCUGCGUCUUGUUGGUGAUAACCUCUGCUGGGAGGUUACUUUGUUGCCUAGAAAGUUCUGGAAUCCACAACCAGGGGCUGGCACUGGAGCCAGCAGCUUGGCCGAGUCACAGGUGACCCGUGGCCCUCACGUCUCUGGUUUUACCUUUCCUUACUUCAUUCAUUCACUCACCCAGUCCUUACGAAUCACCGAGGAACACUGGGCUGAGCACAUGACAGGGAGCCUGGAGCCCCGGGGCCUCCAGCGAGGCCUGAGAAGGGUGGUUCGGGUAACCACUGUGGGCUCUCUCCCAUCACAGAAGGUGGACAGGGCCUACCCAGGUGGAGGGGACCACCCUGCGAUCAGGUGUUUGCGACAGGGGUUGGGCCAGCUGAGGCAAGCUGUCUUUUUUCCCUUUUCUUUUUAAUAGAUGCAACAUUUUUAUAAUAAUCCUAGAGACCUUUUUUCUACCAAAGAUCACAGACCAGAAAAAGUUCCAUCUAAAAUAUCAUGCCCAGGAAAGCACAUGGGAUCAAAAGUAAAAUAGCAUCAUGUGUGAUCUCGUCUUCCAGCGUGCCGCUCAGUUCCCCGAAUCCGUGUGCACACGUGUGAUCUCGUCUUCAGUGUGCCGCUCAGUUCCCUGAAUCCGUGUGCACACUGCGUAUGUGUACGCGCAGCAUGCUAUACUGAACUCAACAAGAUCUUGGCUGUACAUAAAUAUUUGUAAAAGAGACCCUUUGCACCUUUUUACUGUAAUGUUGAGACUUCAUUACUUAAAUGUUCUACGGAAGGUUCUGGUGUGGUUGUUGGAGCCGGAGGGAGCGUGUCAGCACGUGCUGAGGGCAUGGGGCCUGCCCCCUGGGCACCCAUCCACAAGCUGGGCCACGGAGCUCCAGCUUCUCAGGACAAAGCCCCGGGGCUGGCGCAUCCUGAGGGUCUCUGGGGGUGUUUGCCAGGCUCCUGGGAUGGGCCGCUUUCAGAAGCCCUGCAGUGCCUCCAGAUGGAAAGGCGGGCCCGGCCUCCGGUUGGGUCUGCAUUUUGGAGAGUCCACACCACGGACCAGGUUUUCCCCCAAGGCUUGGCUUUGUGUAGCUACUAACUUCUUGGGGCAUUCUGAGAGUGUGGGCAGAGAGAAUUAUGUGGCCUCAUCCUCCCCCAAGGCUGUGCUUGCAGCCCGGGCACCUUCCCACUUUCUAGCUCUGGAGAGGUUGGAUUUUGCUUUUGUAAACACAUGAAUCCUUAUGAUAAAAGUCUGUCAGUCAAAAAUACAUUUAUAAAUUAUUUAAUGCCAGUCCUCAUGUAACCUCAGGUAUCUUCAGCUUGUGGAGAAUAAAUCUGGUUUAAUAAACA